GGUGGGUUUCAUCGGGUGGGCCCAGCGGGACAGGGCCGGGUGAAAUUAGGGAGGGGGCUGGGCUGGGGCGCAAUGGAGGCCGAGCCAAUCCCGGACUCCUCAAUGCCAGCAAAGCUUCUGGCGCCGCCCUGUCUGAACCUGGAGCGGCUGGGAGGAUCCCCCUCCCAGGAGAAGCCGAGGACCCCAGGAUGCUGCAGAAUCAGUGAGAGGUGCGUAAGGCCAAACCCCAUUCCCCGGACCCCGCUAGCACUUCACCACCUGGCUCAGUGAUCAAGGGGUCAUGACCUCUCUUUGCUGGGGUUAUCGAGAAGUGGCAAUUUUAUAAUAGUUACUGAAACUUACAAAGAGGUUCUGGUGCCCAGAGACACUUGGGGUCAUCUAGGGAUCAGAGGCCAUGCAAUUCCAUGUCUCUGGGGCUGAUGUAGGCACUCCCCAGGGAUCAUCCAGGGGUUAUGGAGGGCAACUCAAUAAUAAUGAAAAUGAUAAAAAUCGUAAUCAUAUUAUGGCAAGCCAGCGGCGUGGUGGCGCGUGCCUGUAAGUCCCAGCUACUCGGGAGGCUGAGGCGGAAGGAUCGGUCGAGCCCAGGAGUUCUAGGCUGCACUGAGUCCUGAUCACGCCCCUGCACUCCAGGCGGGGGUACAGAGUGAGGCUCGGUCUCUAAAAGAAACACAAAGAAAAAAAGUAACCUUUUUCUCGAUCCUGCAGCCAGAGGCUUGAUAUCCUGCCUCGGUCACCUAGGGCGGUCCCUGCCUGGGUGAUCUACGGGUGCCGUAAGGGGUUGAUUGAUGUGGAGGGCUGGGCGUGCCUGGGAGGCCCACAGUGGGCGAGGUGAGUUGCAAUUACUGCAACUCUUAAACCUUCCACCCAGAGUUAGAAAUGACUGAACCUCAGGUGGGGUGUGUAGCCUGUCCAAGGGUACACAAAGAGCCGGCCCAAGUUGGAACCCCCUGGCCGGCUAAACCCAGGAGUCACCCAAGAAAACGUGACCCCACUGCCCUUCUCCCCAGGUCCCUCUGGCCUGCAUGCCAGGAGUCGGUCACCGCCCUGUGCUUCCUCCAAGAGACAGUGGAGAGGCUGGGUCAGUCCCCUGCCCAGGACACCCCGGUCCUGGGGCCUUGCUGGGACCCGAUGGCUCUGGGGACUCAGGGCCGCCUGCUGCUGGACAGGGAUUCCAAGGACACACAGACCAGGAUCAGCCAAAAGGGCCGCCGUCUGCAGCCCCCGGGGACUCCCUCGGCCCCACCCCAGAGAAGGCCCCGGAAACAGCUGAACCCCUGCCGGGGCACCGAGAGAGUGGACCCUGGGUUCGAGGGGGUGACUCUGAAGUUUCAGAUAAAGCCGGACUCCAGCCUGCAGAUCAUCCCCACGUACAGCCUGCCCUGCAGUAGCCGUUCUCAGGAAUCCCCUGCAGAUGCUGUUGGGGGCCCUGCAGCCCACCCAGGAGGCACCGAGGCCCACUCAGCAGGCAGCGAGGCCCUGGAGCCCCGGCGCUGUGCUUCCUGUCGGACCCAGAGGACCCCGCUCUGGAGAGACGCUGAAGAUGGGACCCCUCUCUGCAACGCCUGUGGGAUCAGGUACAAGAAAUACGGCACUCGCUGCUCCAGCUGCUGGCUGGUGCCCAGGAAAAAUGUCCAGCCCAAGAGGCUAUGUGGCAGAUGUGGAGUGUCCCUGGACCCCAUUCAGGAAGGUUAAACCCAGCUUCACCCUGCUGAGCUGCUGCUUCUGCCUCCGUUUCACCAGUGGGAGAAUGGGCAGAAGCAGCUCUCCUAGGAGGAUUGGGGAAAGAGCCGGCCUGCCUCCUCUCUGCCAUCUCCAGAUUCAAGGAUCCCGGGGGAAGACCCAGGCCUCAGGUGGCAGAGCCUGCUAGGGGUCACCAGCCCCUUCUCCAGUCAGCCUUGGCCGAGGCCCCCUCAGGAGACGCUCUCAGGAAGGAUGAGCAUUGUUACAGCAGGGACAAUAAAGUACAGAGAUAUGCCGAGA